GCUUCCUCGCCGCCGCGGGCUCAAGCGGGGCGGCCGGGCCAGCGCGGGGCGGCGGCGGGCAGGGGCGGCGAGUGCGCGGGCGCUCGCCGCCGCCCUUCUCGGCGGGCAGCGCGCGAGGACCAGGCCGAGGAGGAAGUGGCGGCGGCGGCGGCGGGACUGCGCGCCCCAGCUCCGAUCCCCGUUCCGCGUCCCCGCCGCCGGGAGGAGGUGCCCACUCGCUCGCGGCGCGCGCCGGCCGCCAGACUCGGCCUGUGGGCGAUUUCCUCCGGACCCAGGCUCCCCGCCCGAGGAGGAAGAUGCAGACCUUUCUGAAAGGGAAGAGAGUUGGCUACUGGCUGAGCGAGAAGAAAAUCAAGAAGCUGAAUUUCCAGGCCUUCGCCGAGCUGUGCAGGAAGCGAGGGAUGGAGGUUGUGCAGCUGAACCUUAGCCGGCCGAUCGAGGAGCAGGGCCCCCUGGACGUCAUCAUCCACAAGCUGACUGACGUCAUCCUUGAAGCCGACCAGAAUGAUAGCCAGUCCCUGGAGCUGGUGCACAGGUUCCAGGAGUACAUCGAUGCCCACCCUGAGACCAUCGUCCUGGACCCGCUCCCUGCCAUCAGAACCCUGCUUGACCGCUCCAAGUCCUAUGAGCUCAUCCGGAAGAUUGAGGCCUACAUGGAAGACGACAGGAUCUGCUCGCCACCCUUCAUGGAGCUCACGAGCCUGUGCGGGGAUGACACCAUGCGGCUGCUGGAGAAGAACGGCUUGACUUUCCCAUUCAUUUGCAAAACCAGAGUGGCUCAUGGCACCAACUCUCACGAGAUGGCUAUCGUGUUCAACCAGGAGGGCCUGAACGCCAUCCAGCCACCCUGCGUGGUCCAGAAUUUCAUCAACCACAACGCCGUCCUGUACAAGGUGUUCGUGGUUGGCGAGUCCUACACCGUGGUCCAGAGGCCCUCACUCAAGAACUUCUCCGCAGGCACAUCAGACCGUGAGUCCAUCUUCUUCAACAGCCACAACGUGUCAAAGCCGGAGUCGUCAUCGGUCCUGACGGAGCUGGACAAGAUCGAGGGCGUGUUCGAGCGGCCGAGCGACGAGGUCAUCCGGGAGCUCUCCCGGGCCCUGCGGCAGGCACUGGGCGUGUCACUCUUCGGCAUCGACAUCAUCAUCAACAACCAGACAGGGCAGCACGCCGUCAUUGACAUCAAUGCCUUCCCAGGCUACGAGGGCGUGAGCGAGUUCUUCACAGACCUCCUGAACCACAUCGCCACUGUCCUGCAGGGCCAGAGCACAGCCAUGGCAGCCACAGGGGACGUGGCCCUGCUGAGGCACAGCAAGCUUCUGGCCGAGCCGGCGGGCGGCCUGGUGGGCGAGCGGACAUGCAGCGCCAGCCCCGGCUGCUGCGGCAGCAUGAUGGGCCAGGACGCGCCCUGGAAGGCUGAGGCCGACGCGGGCGGCACCGCCAAGCUGCCGCACCAGAGACUCGGCUGCAACGCCGGCGUGUCGCCCAGCUUCCAGCAGCAUUGUGUGGCCUCCCUGGCCACCAAGGCCUCCUCCCAGUAGCCACGGAGCCGGGACCCAGAGGGGCAGCGCAGGGCGCAGAGCACACCCGCUGGGCCAGCAGCUCCCAACGGCGAUGCUACUACUAAGAAUCCCCAGUGAUCUGAUUCUUCUGUUUUUUAAUUUUUAACCUGAUUCUCUGAUGUCAUGAUCUAAAUGAGGGGUAGUGGGGGAUGGAAGAGAGUACCAGGUGGUCCACCGUUGGGGAGUGGGGCCGUCCGCCUGCUCUCUACUGUGCAGACCUCCUAACUGAGUUUACACACGCUUGUGUUUGCAACACUAGGUCUGGAUGGGAGGUGAGGGGUGUGCGUAUGGCUGCCAUGCCAGUGUCUGUGCACAUCCCUGUCUGUUGGUCUCCAUGGCCACUGUGGACCGGGACCCUUGGGGGAAGCCUGCCCAUGUCGGGCUGUGGGAGGCUGAUCGGUGCAUGUGAGAGUGGCUUCCCUUCUGCCUGACUCCCCACUCCCUGACCUGCCCCUUCCUUGUUUUUCCUCCUACUGGUCUCCACCAAGGCUUUGUUAGCCCCCACCCUGCCUGGUGUGCAGCUAACCCCUCCCUCCCCACAGCCAGAGGAGGCCACAGACCCCUCAGGGGAGUUCCGCGCUGGGGUCUGGGCUGUGCUCCCUCACUAAAGGGAAGGAAAGGAAGCUGGGCGUCCUCUGGGCCCCCCAACACACGUCCCAUUUAGCCCUGCACAGCGGUCUCCUUCCCCUAAGCCAGCACUGCUGCUCCCUGGAGCCCGGGAAGGAGGCUGCCUGGCUGGAGGCCCGAGCCGAUGGCGCCUGUGCUGAGGAUUUGUGCUGUGAUUUGGGCAAAUCAUUCCAGGUCUUUGGGCCUCCACCCCCUUGUCUCUAGUGGACAUUUGAGAUCAGAGAGCACCACAGGGCUGGCUUUGUGCCCUAACCCCUGGGAUGCAGCCUGCCUUUCCAUAAAGUCACCUAGGUGAGGAUAGGCGCGGGAGCCUCGGCAUGACACCAUGGAGAUCGGGGCCCUCUUCCCAGUGGGUUCACUCCUUUUCACACCUGCUGGGUCCCUCCUCACCCAGCAGGCCUGGUCCACCUCUCAUUGCAAGCCCCAAGCACUGAGCCAGCAGGUGCCAGGGAGCCACCCGCCCCCCAUCGCUUCUGCACACCUCAGACUCACCCCAUCACCUUGGCAGCAAAGCACUGGCUCUGCCGUCUGACCCCUGAUCCAGGCAGCCCCCUCUGCAGAGAAAAGGGUUGGGGAGAAGCCUCUGCAGUCCUGGAAGAUGUGGGGUGCUGGGUGAGAGGCAUCAGCCCCCACAAGUAUGUUUUUGUGUCUUAAGAUAGCAGUUUACUUUGAAAAAGUGAAAAAGGCUUCCGGGCUGUCCUCUGCCCAGUGAGAUGGAGGACGCUAGAGAAAGUGCUGAGUGUCCCGAGAGAGGCCCCCGAGCCAGUGCAUGGAGGUCCUUCGGCCUGGCUCAGCUGGGCUGCAGGAUGCCCACUUUGAGGAGGGAGGCACAGGGCUUGGGCGAGGGGCAGAGGCCAUCAGAACUGCCCGGCUUUUUUGGAAACUGAGGACCCAACAACUAACCACGUUUACACGACUUGAGUUUUGAACCCCGAUUAAUGUCUGUACGUCACCUUUCCUAGUUCUGACCCUGAGCCCUGGGGAACAGGAAAGCGUGGCUGGCCUCUUGCACUGCUUUGUCUCCAAAAUAAACUACUGAAAUCAAACCGCAUUUCACACGUGUUUACACAUGUUGCUCAAGUUUGUUAUGUCAUACUCCCAGUCCUUAAAAGACGUUUAAUAAAACAGCUUUACCUUUUAAAAAUAAAAUUUCAAUCCCAGUCUGCCUCAGGUACGGGUGGGGGUGUGCAGCGUGACUCCUGGCUGUGUUCCUGUACCGUUUGUGGCCUCCGGGGUCUUGCGCGUCCAGGGCCCAGAUACCGAGUAACUGCCAUGUGGUGUCGUGGUGGCGUCCAUAGGCCUCCGUGGUGGGGCGGGGGCGGGGCUGUGGGUGUGCAGGGCAGCUGCAUUUUCCAAGAGUGGAGAUGGAGGAUGGAGAUUUGCUUCGUAAAGGCCUGGGAGCUACAUGGGAGGUAGGGAGGGGCCAGCCACACCCAGGGCUGGGGGGCCGGUGGACUCUGCCCAGUGAAGCCAGGGGAGUGUCAGCAAUGAGGGGCCUGGACAGCGACGCGGGACCCGCACCUGGGAGCGGCAGAGAUGGAGCCCAGCUCGCUAAACGUACCCUAAGGGUGCACGCUGACCAUCUUUGAUCCCUGGACAGUGUCCAUAGAGUUGUCUCCCCUUCGGUCACAUUGUCCCUGGCCUUGGAGUUUCUGCCUCAGGGAAAGACCCACUAAAACCACCCGGGCUCUGGCGGCCUCCUCUUCUCCAGAGCAUGGUGGCGCUGCCUCCUGAGCAGAGUCACUGAGAGUGUCUGGGUCCAAGGAAGGGACCCACUUAGCAAAGGUUGUUGUGUGGUGCUGUGCAGGCACGGCGCCUGGAGUUGGCCCCGCCAGCAUCGGGGUGGCUUGGGGCUCUGGUUCCUAAGCUUCUGCUUCUGAGUUGGUCAGCACGUUGGCUCUGCGCCCUGCAGUGCCUGUCUUGAUGGUGGUCCCUGGAUGUGCUGAAGGGCUCCAGGAGCAAGGGGCCAGACCACACUUUGGCUGAGUCCUUGGGUAGUUUCAGAGGGUCACCUGCACAGUCUGCAUUGAGCACCCUGGGGCUGAGGCCGUGGGUCAAGUUCUGCCUGACAGUGCUUUGAUUAUAUGGUGAUGUGAUUCUGCAAACAUAACCCCCCAACUGAGUGCCAGCUGCUGGGUGUCCCCACCCCAAGAGCCAAGGGGAGGCCACCCUGGAACUGGUGCUUUGCCCUUGGUGUCAUGGAGGUGUCUGGGUCCACACGUGGUGGGUGGGCUGGGCCUGCAGUCACCCAGCAUGGCCGGCGGGAUUGGACCCAGCUGCAACCUGGCAGGUUCCAUGGGGCUUCCUGUGCCUGGGCCUGCCUGUGUCUCAUGCCUGUCAAUAAAGGAGAAAGCAACCUGGGAAAAACAUUCCUCUCUGUACCCAGGGGACUGCCAAGUGUGCUUUAUAGAAGGCUGGAAGACCGACUGAAGUAGGAAGCUGUCACAUGUUUGAGCCAACUGAGCAAAGCAGCUGUUGCCUGCCAGACAGCCACCCCAAGACCAAGGGAGCCAGCCUGUCGUUUGUCCUUCUAGCCUGGAAGACCAGUUCUUGGCUCUUGGGCACUCACAUUGGCCACUGGCCACAACUGCUGAAUGGCUUCACUAAUGUCCCUGGGGUCUGUAUCUGCCCUCUCUUCUAUUCCCUAGAAACUCUGGCCGGGCAUGGCGGCUCACGCCUGUCAUCCCAGCACUUAGGGAGGCUGAGGCAGGUGGAUCACAAGGUCAAGAGAUCGACACCAUCCUGGCCAACAUGGUGAAACCCCAUCUCUACUAAAAAUACAAAAAUUAGCUGGACAUGGUGGUGGGCGCCUGUAGUCCCAGCUACUUGGGAGGCUGAGGCAGGAGAAUUGCUUGAACUCGGGAGGCGUAGGUUGCAGUGAGCCAAGAUCGCACCACUGCACUCCAGCCUGGCAACAGAGCAAGACUCCUCAAAAAACAAACAAACAAACAAACAAACUCUGAUCAUUCACCCGGUGGGAUCCCCGGCAGCUCCUUCUCCUUCCCGAGCUGUGGCUCAUGGGCCAUUGGAUUCAGAGACCUUGAGCUGGGUGCUGGCUGCCCUAAAGGAGCACGACCCCUCCAGCCUGGUGACCGGGAGGCAGAGAAGUGCAGCUGUCCUUGACAAAGGCCCAGCCUCUGCUGCCUCAGGCCAGCCUGGCCACACCCCGAUGCCACAGUCAUCUGCCCCGCCCAGGCAUAAGCCUGACUCAGGUGAUACAGGCGAGGCUUCUCCCAUGGGUCCUCCCCUUGUGAGAAAGGGUCUGUGCUGUGUACCUUCUCUCUGCACAGCCAUUGUCAGUGUGGUUUGGAGUGAGUGAGCCUCCCGCACUGCUCAGGGGAGAGCUGGUGAGCAUGACUCCAUGGCCUCCUGCUGGUUGGGGUCUUCUUCUGAUUCUCACCCGCAGGAGCACCCAGACCCCCCCUUUUCAGAAAUGAUUACAUUUUCCCUUCAAGAGUCAUCUGUGACCUGGUGGUGUGGAGGGACUGUCCCCUCCUGCAGCCUGGCCGACCCCCUUCCUCCAGGGCUGUGUGGAAUCACCUCUCAGAAGCUCACUCUGAAAAGCCACUCACAGGGAUUUCACCAGGAUGUUGCUGUUCCUGCCGACACCUGGGCUUUGUGACAAAUGCUGUUUGCUUCAAGCUGUUCACAAGCAACUUCACCAGAAUCCCAAGCUGGUUCGUACUUAAUUUGUGUACAUACAUAUGCAUAAUAUACAUGACCAUGUAUGAGAUACAGACACCAUGGCUUCUGUCCAUUGGCUCAUUCGCCUGGUCGCAUGUUCACUCCAUGAGGUUAGGACACUGCGGGUGGCUUUGGGAUGGGUGGUUUCAGGGACAAGGUGUCGCUAUGAUCUCUGUAUUUGCUAACUAGUCUUGUUUUGAUUUCUAACGGUCUAGUGGAGUACAGUUAAUGUUGUGUUUAUUUCUGUAACUGUAGGGGUGGAGUAUAAACCUAACUUUUGGAAACAUGAAGAAAUAAACAAUAGCGCCAGCCGUU